GAACCGCCCGCUGCCAGCCCGGCCAGGCACCCCUGCAGCAUGGCCUGGAACACCAACCUCCGCUGGCGGCUGCCGCUCACCUGCCUGCUCCUGCAGGUGAUUAUGGUGAUUCUCUUCGGGGUGUUCGUGCGCUACGACUUCGAGGCCGACGCCCACUGGUGGUCAGAGAGGACGCACAAGAACUUGAGCGACAUGGAGAACGAAUUCUACUAUCGCUACCCAAGCUUCCAGGACGUGCACGUGAUGGUCUUCGUGGGCUUCGGCUUCCUCAUGACUUUCCUGCAGCGCUACGGCUUCAGCGCCGUGGGCUUCAACUUCCUGUUGGCAGCCUUCGGCAUCCAGUGGGCGCUGCUCAUGCAGGGCUGGUUCCACUUCUUACAAGACCGCUACAUCGUCGUGGGCGUGGAGAACCUCAUCAACGCUGACUUCUGCGUGGCCUCUGUCUGCGUGGCCUUUGGGGCAGUUCUGGGUAAAGUCAGCCCCAUUCAGCUGCUCAUCAUGACUUUCUUCCAAGUGACCCUCUUCGCUGUGAAUGAGUUCAUUCUCCUUAACCUGCUAAAGGUGAAGGAUGCAGGAGGCUCCAUGACCAUCCACACAUUUGGCGCCUACUUUGGGCUCACAGUGACCCGGAUCCUCUACCGACGCAACCUAGAGCAGAGCAAGGAGAGACAGAAUUCUGUGUACCAGUCGGACCUCUUUGCCAUGAUUGGCACCCUCUUCCUGUGGAUGUACUGGCCCAGCUUCAACUCAGCCAUAUCCUACCAUGGGGACAGCCAGCACCGAGCCGCCAUCAACACCUACUGCUCCUUGGCAGCCUGCGUGCUUACCUCGGUGGCAAUAUCCAGUGCCCUGCACAAGAAGGGCAAGCUGGACAUGGUGCACAUCCAGAAUGCCACGCUCGCAGGAGGGGUGGCCGUGGGUACCGCUGCUGAGAUGAUGCUCAUGCCUUACGGUGCCCUCAUCAUCGGCUUCGUCUGCGGCAUCAUCUCCACCCUGGGUUUUGUAUACCUGACCCCAUUCCUGGAGUCCCGGCUGCACAUCCAGGACACAUGUGGCAUUAACAAUCUGCAUGGCAUUCCUGGCAUCAUAGGCGGCAUCGUGGGUGCUGUGACAGCGGCCUCCGCCAGCCUUGAAGUCUAUGGAAAAGAAGGGCUUGUCCAUUCCUUUGACUUUCAAGGUUUCAACGGGGACUGGACCGCAAGAACACAGGGAAAGUUCCAGAUUUAUGGUCUCUUGGUGACCCUGGCCAUGGCCCUGAUGGGUGGCAUCAUUGUGGGGCUCAUUUUGAGAUUACCAUUCUGGGGACAACCUUCAGAUGAGAACUGCUUUGAGGAUGCGGUCUACUGGGAGAUGCCUGAAGGGAACAGCACUGUCUACAUCCCUGAGGACCCCACCUUCAAGCCCUCAGGACCCUCAGUACCCUCAGUACCCAUGGUGUCCCCACUACCCAUGGCUUCCUCGGUACCCUUGGUACCCUAGGCUCCCAGGGCAGGUGAGGAGCAGAAAAGAAAAUGGUGCCUGAGAGGCUACAGCAGGACCCGGCAGUGACCCGCUGCUCUUGGCUGUCUCCCUGCAGGCUCCACAGACUGUCCUGGGGCCCAGAGGAGCUGGUGCUGACCUAGCUAGGGAUGCAAGAGUGAGCAAGCAGCACCCCCACCUGCUGGCUUGGCCUCAAGGUGCCUCCACCCCUGCCCUCCCCUUCAUCCCAGGGGGUCUGACUGAGAAUGGAGAAGGAGAAGCUACAAAGUGGGCAUCCAAGCCGGGUUCUGGCUGCAGAAGUUCUGCCUCUGCCUGGGGUCUUGGCCACAUUGGAGAAAAACAGGCUCAAAGUGGGGCUGGGACCUGGUGGGUGAACCUGAGCUCUCCCAGGAGACAACUUAGCUGCCAGUCACCACCUAUGAGGCUCUUCUACCCCGUGCCUGCACCUCGGCCAGCAUCUCCUAUGCUCCCUGGGUCCCCCAGACCUCUCUGUGUUGUGUGCGUGGCAGCCUCCAGGAAUAAACAUUCUUGUUGUCCUUUGUAAAA